ACCCCGCUCUCCGGCCGCCGCCGGUGCGGGUGCUCCGCUACCGGCUCCUCUCCGUUCUGUGCUCUCUUCUGCUCUCGGCUCCCCACCCCCUCUCCCUUCCCUCCUCUCCCCUUGCCUCCCCUCCUCUGCAGCGCCUGCAUUAUUUUCUGCCCGCAGGCUCGGCUUGCACUGCUGCUGCAGCCCGGGGAGGUGGCUGGGUGGGUGGGGAGGAGACUGUGCAAGUUGUAGGGGAGGGGGUGCCCUCUUCUUCCCCGCUCCCUUCCCCCGCCAACUCCUUCCCCUCCUUCUCCCCCUUUCCCCUCCCCGCCCCCACCUUCUUCCUCCUUUCGGAAGGACUGGUAACUUGUCGUGCGGAGCGAACGGCGGCGGCGGCGGCGGCGGCGGCACCAUCCAGGCGGGCACCAUGGGCACGUCCGCGCUCUGGGCGCUCUGGCUGCUGCUCGCGCUGUGCUGGGCGCCCCGGGAGAGCGGCGCCACCGGAACCGGGAGAAAAGCCAAAUGUGAACCCUCCCAAUUCCAGUGCACAAAUGGUCGCUGUAUUACGCUGUUGUGGAAAUGUGAUGGGGAUGAAGACUGUGUUGACGGCAGUGAUGAAAAGAACUGUGUAAAGAAGACGUGUGCUGAAUCUGACUUCGUGUGCAACAAUGGCCAGUGUGUUCCCAGCCGAUGGAAGUGUGAUGGAGAUCCUGACUGCGAAGAUGGUUCAGAUGAAAGCCCAGAACAGUGCCAUAUGAGAACAUGCCGCAUACAUGAAAUCAGCUGUGGCGCCCAUUCUACUCAGUGUAUCCCAGUGUCCUGGAGAUGUGAUGGUGAAAAUGAUUGUGACAGUGGAGAAGAUGAAGAAAACUGUGGCAAUAUAACAUGUAGUCCCGACGAGUUCACCUGCUCCAGUGGCCGCUGCAUCUCCAGGAACUUUGUAUGCAAUGGCCAGGAUGACUGCAGCGAUGGCAGUGAUGAGCUGGACUGUGCCCCGCCAACCUGUGGCGCCCAUGAGUUCCAGUGCAGCACCUCCUCCUGCAUCCCCAUCAGCUGGGUAUGCGACGAUGAUGCAGACUGCUCCGACCAAUCUGAUGAGUCCCUGGAGCAGUGUGGCCGUCAGCCAGUCAUACACACCAAGUGUCCAGCCAGCGAAAUCCAGUGCGGCUCUGGCGAGUGCAUCCAUAAGAAGUGGCGAUGUGAUGGGGACCCUGACUGCAAGGAUGGCAGUGAUGAGGUCAACUGUCCCUCUCGAACUUGCCGACCUGACCAAUUUGAAUGUGAGGAUGGCAGCUGCAUCCAUGGCAGCAGGCAGUGUAAUGGUAUCCGAGACUGUGUCGAUGGUUCCGAUGAAGUCAACUGCAAAAAUGUCAAUCAGUGCUUGGGCCCUGGAAAAUUCAAGUGCAGAAGUGGAGAAUGCAUAGAUAUCAGCAAAGUAUGUAACCAGGAGCAGGACUGCAGGGACUGGAGUGAUGAGCCCCUGAAAGAGUGUCAUAUAAACGAAUGCUUGGUAAAUAAUGGUGGAUGUUCUCAUAUCUGCAAAGACCUAGUUAUAGGCUACGAGUGUGACUGUGCAGCUGGGUUUGAACUGAUAGAUAGGAAAACCUGUGGAGAUAUUGAUGAAUGCCAAAAUCCAGGAAUCUGCAGUCAAAUUUGUAUCAACUUAAAAGGCGGUUACAAGUGUGAAUGUAGUCGUGGCUAUCAAAUGGAUCUUGCUACUGGCGUGUGCAAGGCAGUAGGCAAAGAGCCAAGUCUGAUCUUCACUAAUCGAAGAGACAUCAGGAAGAUUGGCUUAGAGAGGAAAGAAUAUAUCCAACUAGUUGAACAGCUAAGAAACACUGUGGCUCUCGAUGCUGACAUUGCUGCCCAGAAACUAUUCUGGGCCGAUCUAAGCCAAAAGGCUAUCUUCAGUGCCUCAAUUGAUGACAAGGUUGGUAGACAUGUUAAAAUGAUCGACAAUGUCUAUAAUCCUGCAGCCAUUGCUGUUGAUUGGGUGUACAAGACCAUCUACUGGACUGAUGCGGCUUCUAAGACUAUUUCAGUAGCUACCCUAGAUGGAACCAAGAGGAAGUUCCUGUUUAACUCUGACUUGCGAGAGCCUGCCUCCAUAGCUGUGGACCCACUGUCUGGCUUUGUUUACUGGUCAGACUGGGGUGAACCAGCUAAAAUAGAAAAAGCAGGAAUGAAUGGAUUCGAUAGACGUCCACUGGUGACAGCGGAUAUCCAGUGGCCUAACGGAAUUACACUUGACCUUAUAAAAAGUCGCCUCUAUUGGCUUGAUUCUAAGUUGCACAUGUUAUCCAGCGUGGACUUGAAUGGCCAAGAUCGUAGGAUAGUACUAAAGUCUCUGGAGUUCCUAGCUCAUCCUCUUGCACUAACAAUAUUUGAGGAUCGUGUCUACUGGAUAGAUGGGGAAAAUGAAGCAGUCUAUGGUGCCAAUAAAUUCACUGGAUCAGAGCUAGCCACUCUAGUCAACAACCUGAAUGAUGCCCAAGACAUCAUUGUCUAUCAUGAACUUGUACAGCCAUCAGGUAAAAAUUGGUGUGAAGAAGACAUGGAGAAUGGAGGAUGUGAAUACCUAUGCCUGCCAGCACCACAGAUUAAUGAUCACUCUCCAAAAUAUACCUGUUCCUGUCCCAGUGGGUACAAUGUAGAGGAAAAUGGCCGAGACUGUCAAAGUACUGCAACUACUGUGACUUACAGUGAGACAAAAGAUACGAACACAACAGAAAUUUCAGCAACUAGUGGACUAGUUCCUGGAGGGAUCAAUGUGACCACAGCAGUAUCAGAGGUCAGUGUUCCCCCAAAAGGGACUUCUGCCGCAUGGGCCAUUCUUCCUCUCUUGCUCUUAGUGAUGGCAGCAGUAGGUGGCUACUUGAUGUGGCGGAAUUGGCAACACAAGAACAUGAAAAGCAUGAACUUUGACAAUCCUGUGUACUUGAAAACCACUGAAGAGGACCUCUCCAUAGACAUUGGUAGACACAGUGCUUCUGUUGGACACACGUACCCAGCAAUAUCAGUUGUAAGCACAGAUGAUGAUCUAGCUUGACUUCUGUGACAAAUGUUGACCUUUGAGGUCUAAACAAAUAAUACCCCCGUCGGAAUGGUAACCGAGCCAGCAGCUGAAGUCUCUUUUUCUUCCUCUCGGCUGGAAGAACAUCAAGAUACCUUUGCGUGGAUCAAGCUUGUGUACUUGACCGUUUUUAUAUUACUUUUGUAAAUAUUCUUGUCCACAUUCUACUUCAGCUUUGGAUGUGGUUACCGAGUAUCUGUAACCCUUGAAUUUCUAGACAGUAUUGCCACCUCUGGCCAAAUAUGCACUUUCCCUAGAAAGCCAUAUUCCAGCAGUGAAACUUGUGCUAUAGUGUAUACCACCUGUACAUACAUUGUAUAGGCCAUCUGUAAAUAUCCCAGAGAACAAUCACUAUUCUUAAGCACUUUGAAAAUAUUUCUAUGUAAAUUAUUGUAAACUUUUUCAAUGGUUGGGACAAUGGCAAUAGGACAAAACGGGUUACUAAGAUGAAAUUGCCAAAAAAAUUUAUAAACUAAUUUUGUACGUAUGAAUGAUAUCUUUGACCUCAAUGGAGGUUUGCAAAGACUGAGUGUUCAAACUACUGUACAUUUUUUUUCAAGUGCUAAAAAAUUAAACCAAGCAGCUUAACCAUGGUUUGUGCCUGUUCCUCUAGGAUGAACUCCUAUCCUGAGUAGUACCAAGUGUUCUAACUAAAUGUGUGAGCUGUAGUUCUUGAUGUUGUAUAACUAAGCCUGUAAUUGGGCUGGUUUCUCUUACACCCUAGCACAGUUAAAAAAUGAAGUACUGUUUAACAUUUGCUCCCGAAAUAUUUCUUACUGUGUAAAAGAAGCUAGCUUAGUCUGUACCUAGAAUUCCUCUUGGUUAGAGGAGUGAGUUUCUUUUUUUUCCAUUAACUUGUUUCCUGAUCGAGAAACACGUGCUAAGAUUUCUAUGAAUUCUGCUUCUUUAUAGUUAAGUCUCUGUUUUCCAUGUUCUGUCAUUUAUAUAGGUCAAGGACAAGUGCCUUCUAAGGCAUGGAUAAGGGCUUUCUUCUUAUGAAAGUCUAGACUGUCUUACUGUGAAGAUGGCCAGGGAGGAUAGCAAGCAAUGGCAUUCUUGAACAGUCUAAGGCAGGUUUCUCAGUGUGGUCCUGAGAACAGAAGCAUCUGCAUCACCUGGGAAUGUAUUAGAAAUGCAAGUUCCCAGCCCCAUCCCAGACCUACUGAAUCAGAAACUCUGGGGGCGAGGGCUGAAACCUGCUUUCAUAAGCCCUUCAGGCGAUACUGAUGUAAACUAAAGCUUAAAAACCACCGUUUUACUGUGACUUCAUGAAGAAUAUAAUUGCAAUAUCACCUAAAUUUUUAUCCUGGCUGGGAUGGGGCAGAUUCUUACUAUGGACAAUUUCUGGAACUUACAGUAUGAAGAGCAGAUGAGGAGUUUGAGACAAAGAAAAAAUUGUACAGGGAGUUUAGUGAAUUUUCCAUCAGGUUGGCCAUUACUUUCUUUCUCUAAAGUCUCAGGAUGUCUGGAAGCAAGGAAAGACAAAAGACUUGAAGCACCGGGUGCAUGCUGUGUGUCACAAGUGAGGUGGAGAGUUGGCUGUGGAAGGUACAGCAAUUCCUCUGGAAUUAAAUGACCGACCAACACAGUACCAAGAGGAUGAAGAGAAGAUGUUUUGCGUUGCUACGUGAAUCAGUGGAUGACUCAUAUUUCACUUGCAUAUGAAAUAUAAGGCAGUUAACAUCUUGUUUGUGGCUUAAGCAAGGACAUUAAUCCUACUAGAUGAAGGGGAAGUUGGUUCUGUUGUCUUAAGGGAUGCCCCCUUGUGAUUUUGGUCAACUGAAUGAAAAAGAAAAGAUAGCCUUGGACUUUUUUUUCAUGGGAGGUUUGGAGGUCAAGCAUGUAGAAGGAAAAGGCUGUAGUCAUGAAUAUAGAACUGUCUGCUCUCCACCUUUUCCUCACUCUACAUUUAGUCAUCACACUGAACAGGAUGUGGCCUGCUGACAGUGAGUAGCUGAAGUGCCUGUUUGGUAAGUAGGUUAGCAUUCAUCAUGAACUCUGAAAGCCAUUUCAGAGUUUGGCUGCUGCUCUGACCCUGCUGUGGUACAAAAAACAUGGAUUUUUUUUUUUUUAACUGGAGUAAUACCAAAUUCCCUUUAGAAGCUUGAAGUUUGAUACUAUUGCUUUCCCCAUUAUAAGGAUUAUACAGUAUUAAUUAAUUAUAAGGCCCAAAGUUUGUUUUGGCAAAUAAAGUAUUAUUCUCUAUCAUCAUCUUUUGAAUUCCUGUCCCUAGUAUGUUCUUUCAUGUUCUGGGUAAAAUUUCCAACCCUCAAAGAGUCUAAAACGUCUCAUUUUUUUUUACCACGUCCUCCCCAGUAAGAAGCCAAGGUACAACUCAUUGUACCUACGAGGUACAAACUCAUUUGUAGAAACAAAGUAACUAGAUAUUCCUAUUGAAAUAAGAAUAGAUAUAUUGGUGGGCCAGGCAUGGUGGCUCACGCCUAUAAUCCCAGCACUUUGGAAGGCCAAGGCAGGAGGAUCACUUGAGGCCAGGAGUUCGAGACCAGCCUGAGCAACAUGGUGAGACCCUGUCUCUACAAAAAAAAAAUUUAUAAAAAUAAAAGAAAAAAAUAGUUAUAUGACUAAACUACUAGUCAAUACAGCUUGCAAUAAUAGUGCAUGAAUGAUAACAGGCCUCGGCUUUAUCACCCAAAAAAUAACUUGAAUUCUAUGUGAAAUGUGUUAGGAUAAGUUUGCUCUGUCUCUAGAGUUCAAUGUAGAAGAUAAUUAAGAGGUAAAAUAUGAAGCUUAUCAUACACUAAAGGAGAAUAUUUGGAGUUAGAUGAGCCUGUCACACAAAGUGAAAGUGGACCCUCCAGAAAUUUUAGGAAUUGCCACAAAGAUUGAUGAUAGAUGAAUAAACAGAUUUGUGGCCUCUGGUAAAGAAAUCCAGCCAAGUUCCUCUGUCCAAAUUUUUAAGUGCCCUUUGCAAGCUAAUCUAUUUGGCAAAAAAAUAGUCCCAGUUGUUCAACUAGCUCCCUUAAAACAUUCUAGUAGGUGUUUUAAAGCCUAGGUAUCGCUGCCUCUUUAGUUCUUGAUGAAUACAAGGCAAAAAAAAAAAAAAAAAAAAAAAAAAAAUUGAGGCUUUCACUUUGGCAUUUGCUUCUGUUCCUUGUAUCUGUGGAAGUCAAGUAGCCCUUCUCAAAAAUGAGAAGCCAAGCUUUAAAUAGCAAACUACAGGGUAUUAAAAGACUAACUCUUCAGUUAAGAACACUGUAGAAAUGGUAGACCAACUUAAAGUCUACCUUUUAACAAUCUUUACCCCAAACCUAAAGAUUCUAGGGGUCACUUAUCUCUAUUACGUAAUCUAACUGGAAUAAUUUCCUAGAAUUCUUACUAGUGAAAUCUUACCCAAGUAAAACAAUUUAUUAUUUUGAAUCCAAAUGAAAGCUAUACUGUUUGCUUUCAAUGGUGGCAAAAACUUGCAAAAAGCAGAUAUACUUUUGCUAAUUUAAGUUGAAGUACUAUGAAUACAACCUGCUAAUCUUGAUCCCCAAAUCUGAGCCCUUCAGUUUCAUAAUUGUUUUAUCCUGAACGUAGUUGUGACAUAGACAUUUCUCAAAAGGGUCUGAUACAUCAAACUCCUAACAAGUAGGAGCAGCAACUAGCUAAAGAGUAGAAAGAAGCUUCCCUUAUUGUGGGUGAUGAGGCGGUGCCUAAAAACCACAUAUAUAUAAUCCCCUGGGUAUUACAUAUUCUGCAAGCCCUGUUAGUGGGGAGAUGGUAGUGGCAAUAGCAGCGAUAGUUGCGUCAGUGCUAACUGCUGCUGCUGCCCGUUCUGUUGGCGGCUGCUGGCCAAGUGUGCACACUUAGCCCUGGUUGAGGUGCAUUGUCUGCUGUCGUCUGUUAAGCAUCUAACCGGAGUGGGAGGGCACAUCAAGCGAUUUCACUCUCUUAAAGAAAAGGUUUUUAGGUAUUUUUGGUAUUAUAUAGUCUCUAAGGCCAGAAGGGGCUUAUAAUGACUUCUCUUCUAGAAUUGUAAUACUAAAAAACUACUCGAGUAAAUAUCCUAACAAGUAUGAUUUUUCUUGGGAAAACUAAAAAUUGUACAUCCAUGCUUCAGCCAUAUCAUGGGCCUAAACUAUGAGAGUUCAGAAAUAUAUAAAAGUACAAAAAUCUUCAAAGGUACUUAUUUCCAAAUAUGGAGGGAAUGAAUCUGAAGAGGGAACAAUGGCGUUUUUCGAACUUAUUUCUCUCUAAUCCAGCCUGGAGGAUUUUUAGCCGAAACAGUUGCAUGUGAAGGAUUAUCAGCCAUCUUUGCAUAUCCCUUUCACAUCUACCUUCACACAGGAAAGCUGAAUGCAUUUUACCAGUGAGGCUCUAGAUAUGAAACUUAGGGAUCCAUAGAUAAAUAAGCUACUAACAAACUGAUAACAGUGGUGUUCCAUCUCUCUAUCAUGUCUCCUGAGUCCGUUUCACGUUUUUGAGCCUGGCUAAUGAGAAAAAGAACAAAGUAGGACCAUGACCCAGUGUUCUCCUGUAAAUCUCACUGUAAAAAUCUCAAUGCAAAAACACUGAGACAGGAGUGAGACCAGCUGCGGGUGGGGAGUUUGUGCUCCGCAGGUUACCUCAUGGCAUAUCAAAAAUGGCUUUUUUCUUCACUGCGCUCAAGGAAAAAGUCAGAUGGGUGACAAGGUGGUUCUGUUUAGAAGCAGCAGGCAAUGUAGUUAACAGCAUAGACUUCCGUGUCUUGUGUGUGGUACCUUGGGCAAGUUACUAACUCCCUCUGUAAAGUAGAGACGAUGGGGACUGUCUCACUGUGACAAGGUAAGAUUUAAGUGAGAUGCACACAAAAAGCUCAGCACAGUGUCUGGCAUCUAAUAUGUGCAGGGCAGAUGUCACUACUGAAUAUCACAUCAAUGCUAGGGCUGUAUUUACUGUCACACACAGGCACCGGUAAGUGACUUUACCGGUGAAAGUCACAGGUACCUUUAUCUAUGAUGAAUGUAAUGUGUUAGAUGGUGACCGAAGUGUUCUCCACUACACCUGUCUGAAGAGAUCUAAGUCUGAUAUUUAAGGAGUGAUAGCAUCUUGCAUACUUAAGAAGGCUUAAAAGACUGCAUGGUUUAAACCCUAGAAACAUAAAUGGAAUGUUUCUGCCUCAGUUCUUUUGACUACCUCCUAGGACAUGGAAACAAAUAUUUGGGAGCCUGCAUAGUCUUUAGAUGGCUGCCAAAGCACUUAAAAUCUCCUUUAAAUUCUUACCAUAUGCUUACUUUUGUACUAAGUAAGUGCUCCCAAGUCUUUUACUUGCUCUUCACAGCAACCCUAAUAGGUAUCUCCAUUUUACAUAGGUAAAAACUGAGGCUACAAACAAUCUAUGGUUCCAAAUCCUAUGUGCUUACUGCCGUCUUCUCUUAGAAGGGGAUGCAGUACUGUACAAAGAUUGAGCUGGAUGUCGCAUUGCAUGUUUGCUGAGUCCUCCUCAUUGCUGAUGUUAGGAUCCUUCAACAGUUUCUCAGAUGCCAGCUAUGGCUGGCAUCCAGUAUGGUGGUGUAAUGGAAGUGUACUACUAGCACUACUACAUCAGGUCAGCACAGAUUAACUCAGUUACGUGUUAUACCUUCAAGACGCUAGACAUUCCAGAAUUAUUUUCCUUGGCCAUCCAAGUGAAGUAGAAGUAGAUUGUUGGAUUGCAAAGAAAAUGAUAAAGAUUCCCUAAAGGAAUUUAUAAGCAGGCAACUUCAUUCCUAUGUAUAAGAUAUUGGGAGAAAACAAACUGUACCACAACAAAUCUUAAGUUUCAAGGCUCUCCUAUAGGGAGAAACAUGGCCAAAAAGACAGGAAGAACUGUGGCUUGUAACUCAAUGAUGCUAUAACUCCAGCACUGGAUCUUAAGUAUUCUGGAAUAUACCAGAUUGGUAGAACUACCAGACUUGGGUAUUUCUCAGUUAACACACAUGCAAGGAGGAAGAGAGUUUUUUUGAACAAAAUGACUGGCUUUGACAAAACUAUCUUGCUCUUUUUAAAUGUCACUUGAUACUAGAAUGCGAUUUAAAAGCAUGUAAUGCCUCAGGAGUCCGGCAUAUACAACCAAAUUAUCAUGCUCAGGAUCUUCAGAAUUCUAAAGGCACAUGUUAGAAUGCAGAGUCCUGAUGACCUGUCAAUAAACUUUUUUUUACUAAUGAACUGUACAUUUAAAUAAAAGUUUAUUUUUGGGAUAA